GCACUCCACUGACCGUCCCGACGAUGCUACGCGCGCCCGGCUGCCUCCUCCGGACCUCCGUAGCGCCUGCCGCGGCCCUGGCUGCGGCGCUGCUCUCGUCGCUUGCGCGCUGCUCUCUUCUAGAGCCGAGGGACCCGGUGGCCUCGUCGCUCAGCCCCUAUUUCGGCACCAAGACUCGCUACGAGGAUGUCAACCCCGUGCUAUUGUCGGGCCCCGAGGCUCCGUGGCGGGACCCUGAGCUGCUGGAGGGGACCUGCACCCCGGUGCAGCUGGUCGCCCUCAUUCGCCACGGCACCCGCUACCCCACGGUCAAACAGAUCCGCAAGCUGAGGCAGCUGCACGGGUUGCUGCAGGCCCGCGGGUCCAGGGAUGGCGGGGCUAGUAGUACCGGCAGCCGCGACCUGGGUGCAGCGCUGGCCGACUGGCCUUUGUGGUACGCGGACUGGAUGGACGGGCAGCUAGUAGAGAAGGGACGGCAGGAUAUGCGACAGCUGGCGCUGCGUCUGGCCUCGCUCUUCCCGGCCCUUUUCAGCCGUGAGAACUACGGCCGCCUGCGGCUCAUCACCAGUUCCAAGCACCGCUGCAUGGAUAGCAGCGCCGCCUUCCUGCAGGGGCUGUGGCAGCACUACCACCCUGGCUUGCCGCCGCCGGACGUCGCAGCCUUUUCUAGCUAUUCUCAUGCGUUACAGCCAUUAUAAAUGGGGAAUAAUUUUACCCCAAGAGUUUCCUGACCAAUAUGUGCUUAUUUCAGCUGUGCGGAUUAGUAAGAUAUAUGGAGUUUGGACCUCCAACAGUUAAUGAUAAACUAAUGAGAUUUUUUGAUCACUGUGAGAAGUUUUUAACUGAAGUAGAAAAAAAUGCUACAGCUCUUUAUCACGUGGAAGCCUUCAAAACUGGACCAGAAAUGCAGAACAUUUUAAAAAAAGUUGCAGCUACUUUGCAAGUGCCAGUAAAUGAUUUAAAUGCAGAUUUAAUUCAAGUAGCCUUUUUCACCUGUUCAUUUGACCUGGCAAUUAAAGGUGUUAAAUCUCCUUGGUGUGAUGUUUUUGACAUAGAUGAUGCAAAGGUAUUAGAAUAUUUAAAUGAUCUGAAACAAUAUUGGAAAAGAGGAUAUGGGUAUACUAUUAACAGUCGAUCCAGCUGCACCUUGUUUCAGGAUAUCUUUCAGCACUUGGACAAAGCAGUUGAACAGAAACAAAGGUCUCAGCCAAUUUCUUCUCCAGUCAUCCUCCAGUUUGGUCAUGCAGAGACUCUUCUUCCACUGCUUUCUCUCAUGGGCUACUUCAAAGACAAGGAACCCCUAACAGCGUACAAUUACAAAAAACAAAUGCAUCGGAAGUUCCGAAGUGGUCUCAUUGUACCUUAUGCCUCGAACCUGAUAUUUGUGCUUUACCACUGUGAAAAUGCUAAGACUCCUAAAGAACAAUUCCGAGUGCAGAUGUUAUUAAAUGAAAAGGUGUUACCUUUGGCUUACUCACAAGAAACUGUUUCAUUUUAUGAAGAUCUGAAGAACCACUACAAGGACAUCCUUCAGAGUUGUCAAACCAGUGAAGAAUGUGAAUUAGCAAGGGCUAACAGUACAUCUGAUGAACUAUGAGUAACUGAAGAACAUUUUUAAUUCUUUAGGAAUCUGCAAUGAGUGAUUACAUGCUUGUAAUAGGUAGGCAAUUCCUUGAUUACAGGAAGCUUUUAUAUUACUUGAGUAUUUCUGUCUUUUCACAGAAAAACAUUGGGUUUCUCUCUGGGUUUGGACAUGAAAUGUAAGAAAAGAUUUUUCACUGGAGCAGCUCUCUUAAGGAGAAACAAAUCUAUUUAGAGAAACAGCUGGCCCUGCAAAUGUUUACAGAAAUGAAAUUCUUCCUACUUAUAUAAGAAAUCUCACACUGAGAUAGAAUUGUGAUUUCAUAAUAACACUUGAAAAGUGCUGGAGUAACAAAAUAUCUCAGUUGGACCAUCCUUAACUUGAUUGAACUGUCUAGGAACUUUACAGAUUGUUCUGCAGUUCUCUCUUCUUUUCCUCAGGUAGGACAGCUCUAGCAUUUUCUUAAUCAGGAAUAUUGUGGUAAGCUGGGAGUAUCACUCUGGAAGAAAGUAACAUCUCCAGAUGAGAAUUUGAAACAAGAAACAGAGUGUUGUAAAAGGACACCUUCACUGAAGCAAGUCGGAAAGUACAAUGAAAAUAAAUAUUUUUGGUAUUUAUUUAUGAAAUAUUUGAACAUUUUUUCAAUAAUUCCUUUUUACUUCUAGGAAGUCUCAAAAGACCAUCUUAAAUUAUUAUAUGUUUGGACAAUUAGCAACAAGUCAGAUAGUUAGAAUCGAAGUUUUUCAAAUCCAUUGCUUAGCUAACUUUUUCAUUCUGUCACUUGGCUUCGAUUUUUAUAUUUUCCUAUUAUAUGAAAUGUAUCUUUUGGUUGUUUGAUUUUUCUUUCUUUCUUUGUAAAUAGUUCUGAGUUCUGUCAAAUGCCGUGAAAGUAUUUGCUAUAAUAAAGAAAAUUCUUGUGACUUUACUACCAGGACUUUUCUCUUCCCCAUGUCAAAAUACAAUCAAUAAUUGAUGGUAAAAGUUUGGAAAUUCAAGCA